GUAUCUCCUCCGUCCCCUCCUGCCGCGCGGCGUGAGCGCCGGGCUCGGGGCCCCCCCGGCCGCCCGCCCCCUCCCCUCCCUCCCUCCCCUCCCCUCCCCUCCCCCCCGGGCCCCGCGCCCCCCCCGCCCCCGCCCCCCCCAUGGACAUGCUGGACCCGGGUCUGGAUCCCGCUGCCUCGGCCACCGCUGCUGCCGCCGCCAGCCACGACAAGGGACCCGAGGCGGAGGAGGGCGUCGAGCUGCAGGAAGGCGGGGACGGCCCAGGAGCGGAGGAGCAGACAGCGGUGGCCAUCACCAGCGUCCAGCAGGCGGCGUUCGGCGACCACAACAUCCAGUACCAGUUCCGCACAGAGACAAAUGGAGGACAGGUGACAUACCGCGUAGUCCAGGUGACUGAUGGUCAGCUGGACGGCCAGGGCGACACAGCUGGCGCCGUCAGCGUCGUGUCCACCGCUGCCUUCGCGGGGGGGCAGCAGGCUGUGACCCAGGUGGGUGUGGACGGGGCAGCCCAGCGCCCGGGCCCCGCCGCUGCCUCUGUGCCCCCAGGUCCUGCAGCGCCCUUCCCGCUGGCUGUGAUCCAAAAUCCCUUCAGCAAUGGUGGCAGUCCGGCGGCCGAGGCUGUCAGCGGGGAGGCACGAUUUGCCUAUUUCCCAGCGUCCAGUGUGGGAGAUACUACGGCUGUGUCCGUACAGACCACAGACCAGAGCUUGCAGGCUGGAGGCCAGUUCUACGUCAUGAUGACGCCCCAGGAUGUGCUUCAGACAGGAACACAGAGGACGAUCGCCCCCCGGACACACCCUUACUCUCCAAAAAUUGAUGGAACCAGAACACCCCGAGAUGAGAGGAGAAGAGCCCAGCACAACGAAGUUCCUUGAAAUUCGAUGAGACUUACCCGACGGGCCCGAAUGUGUCCUAGCUUGGCGGAAGCUUCUGGGGCAUUGACGAGGACAGGUGUCUGCUGCUGUCAGGCAGAAUGUCCCCCCAGGUCAGUGAGGUCAGGCUGGUUGAGUGUUCAGGCUUUCUAUUCUGAUUUUUGUUGUUGUUGUUUACUUGUUCCACCAAUCAAUGAGAAAGAUGUCCAUGUCUCUCACUAUAUUUGUGGAUUUGUCCAUUUCUUCCUUCAGUCCUGGCAGGUUUCGCUUCUGAAUUUUCUCUUUUUUUUUUUUUUUUUUUUGAGACAGAGUCUCGCUCUGUCACCCAAGCUGGUGUGCAAUGAUGUGGUCUCGGCUCACUACAACCUCCACCUCUUGGGUUCAAGCAAUUCUCGUGCUUCAGCCUCCCAAGUCGCUGGGAUUAUAGGCAUGCACUGCUAUGCCUGGCUAAUUUUUGCAUUUUUAGUAGAGCCGGGGUUUCGCCAUGUUGGCCAGGCUGGUCUCAAACUCCUGGCCUCAUGUGAUCCACCCUCCCAAAGUGCUGGGAUUACAGGCGUGAGCCACCCCACCCAGCUUCUGAAUUUUAAGUUUCCUAUGGAGUAACUGAAGUGCUUCUGUGGAAUGAACGUGGCCUUGGUCCUAAUGGGUCUUCCUGUAUUUCAAAUGUGCCAUGAUGGUCUUCCGAAGCCACAGGCUGGACAGCAUUACCGCCUGCUAAUGUCAGGGCCUGGAUUCAAGGGCCUGGGACUCUGGAGGAGGAGGAGAUGCGGUCCUGACCUGCGAGCAGAGCACACAAGGCCUUGACAACCGAUCUUUACAACCUUUUCCCACCCCUGCAUACCCUGAAAUGGUUUUCAGGCCACCAUUUCUGGGAUCUUCCCAGCUGCCUGCCUUAGAGUCUUUCUCUCAGAAACCAGCCCGAAUGUUUCCUGGAUCUCUGAGGAUUCAUCCCACCCCCAUUCCCAUGCAGAGGCCAUGGCUCGGCGCCUGGCGUUCCCGAGGCACUUUGUACCAUCUUCAGUGAUGACACGAAUGCAAUGGGGUUAGUGCCACUUGCCCACAGUGGUGCUGCGAGUGCCCAUGGGGCGCACCGGGGCUGCUUCCACCCUGGACCCCAGCCUGGCGGAGGGCCUGGCACAUAGUAGGGCGGGGAGUAGGUGUGUAAGAAGUAAGCUUGCUCUGGAGAGGAUGUACCUGCAGCCGGCGCCCAGCUCUCGAGAGGACUGUGGGAGGGCAGAGGCUGAAACGAGGCCGCCUGCCGAGUUCCUCCACAGACCCCUGGGCGAGGAGCGCUCUGCUGGGGACUGCGCCAGCGGUGCCUCCAGGCCUGGACUCUCAGCUCCGCUGCUGCUUUUGGCCAGAGUUCCCAAAGGCGGGUGUGGUUGUCUUUGGUGGGAAGGUUCAGCGCACCGCGAUAGUAAUAGGGGAGCAAGCACUCGCUGAGCCCAGUGCAGGGCCUGGACCGUGCUCCAUAGCAAGCACUGAUCUUGGGCUAUUGGUUUUGGAGGAAAGAGGGAGCACAAGGAUGGAAGGGGCCAGGGAAGAGAGGUCACGGUGGGAGAAGGAGAGUCCGCAUCCAUCGGAGGGUUUGUCACUCAGGCCUGAGUGGGAGGCACUGGAGGCAGGGAGAGGCCAGUCAGCAGCAUGCGGCCACAGCCCAGAGAAGCCAGAGGGGUUUGCUGGUGGGUGGGCCCCAGCCUUUUCAAGGGAACGGCAGGUCUGGGGAGCUGCCGAUCUCGGGGUGUGAGGGUAACGGGCAGGCUGUGGCCCACCCCUCCUUCUCAGGCUCACUGGACCCCUGACCGGUUUCAUCACCAUUAUCCAAGGCUUUGAAAAGACCCCCUGGCCUUCCUGCCACAUGUGCCCUAGCUAUAGGGCUUCGUUCCCCUCCACAAAUGGUGCAGACAGCAUGAGCCACCCUGGCAGGGGGCUGGGGGUCCGUGGGGUAGGAGUUGGGGGUAGCUGAGCGUUCUUUCCUGUCCCCACGGUGCCUGGUGCUGGGGCUUGGCAGCCAGGGUUGGGACAGCCUGGCUUUAGCAGGUCCUGAGUCAGGGGUCUCAGGCUCCGCAGCACACAGUCCCCAGGCAGGUGUCAGGAUGGGAUGUGGCCAGAGAAAGGCAUGUGCUCUGUCUGGGGAUAGCUGCCACCCAGCUGACACAGUUGGCAUGAGAUUGUGGAGUUUUAUGGAGUAAAAUCACAAAUCUGGGUUUUUUAAGUAAAACCUUCUAUGAGUUGCCAUCUCUGGCCUUCAACAUAGGAUUUGGGUCUUUCCUGGGUGAGCUGGUGCUUUGUGGGCCAGGCCCUGGGAGCUGCAAGUACCAGUUGGGAUCUGCCAUUGCCCUGUGGAAGGAUUUUAAGCAGGGGUGAAACAUGGUCAGACUUGGAUUUAGAGAUGAGGAAAAAAAACAAAAUCACGGUGCCAGAGUCUCUGGGGAGACUGGAGAAUGCAGUGCAGGGGCCGCAGGAGCCAAAAAGGGGCACUGGUCCUGCGAAGAGUGGCUCUGUCCAUCCCUGCCUUCCAGUAUGUGCCCACUGUGACCAGAGCUCCAUUUCUCAAAAGAAGCCAGUGAUGCCAAUUACCAUGAGAAAUUUCCUUAUUUUUAACUGUCGAUUAAAAUUUGUACAAGUAUGGUGGGGCAGGCCUGCAAAAUGAUCUCCAAGUGCCUGGCCUUUGAUGCCCGUCCUAAAAGCAUGUGUGGCACUGGAGGGCCCACGUUUCUUUGUUCCUCUUGAGAAGCUGGGGUGGGGGCCGGCUGGGCUCAGGGUGCGGCCCCUCACU